GCGAGCGCACCGCCCUCGGGUGGAGCUAGUGCUCAGGGCGUCCUCGUGCCUUUUCUUGGUGGCGGGAAACCUGGGUUGAGGUGUGAGGGGCUUGCGGAGUCGCUGCGGCAGCUGGUUCCGCCCAUCGCCUUUAGGUCCUCCUUGCUCCUGAAGCUUUCAGUAUUUGUUAUUGUGAAAGAAGUUAAUUCACCUGAAACAGAGGAGGGGCAACCUGAGUUAUCAGAAAGUGACUUCCUGGCCUUCCCUUCUUUACUGAUCAGAGGCACACAAAGCGUAGUUUCUAAGCUGAAUGAUGACAACGUUGCAGAAUAAAGAAGAAUGUGGAAAGGGACCAAAGAGAAUCUUUGCCCCACCUGCACAAAAAUCUUACAGCCUGUUACCUUGUAGCCCUAACUCCCCUAAGGAGGAGACCCCGGGGAUCAGUUCCCCAGAGACAGAGGCCAGGAUAAGCCUGCCAAAGGCCAGUUUAAAGAAGAAAGAGGAAAAAGCAACCAUGAAGAAUGUUCCAAGCAGGGAACAGGAGAAAAAAAGAAAGGCACAAAUCAACAAGCAAGCAGAGAAGAAAGAAAAGGAAAAAUCAAGUCUUACCAAUGCAGAAUUUGAGGAGAUUGUCCAGAUUGUUCUGCAGAAGUCCCUUCAGGAGUGCUUGGGGAUGGGAUCUGGCCUUGAUUUUGCAGAGACUUCUUGUGCCCAGCCCGUAGUAUCUACCCAAUCAGACAAGGAGCCAGGAAUUACUGCUUCUGCUACUGAUACUGAUAAUGCUAAUGGAGAGGAGGUACCACAUACUCAAGAGAUUUCAGUGUCUUGGGAAGGUGAAGCUGCCCCUGAGAUAAGGACAUCUAAGUUAGGCCAGCCAGAUCCUGCACCCUCUAAGAAGAAAUCCAAUAGACUCACCUUAAGCAAAAGAAAGAAGGAAGCUCAAGAUGAGAAGGUGGAGAAAACUCAAGGUGGACAUGAGCACAGACAGGAAGACCGACUAAAGAAAACAGUUCAGGAUCAUUCUCAGAUCAGGGACCAGCAAAAAGGAGAGAUAAGUGGUUUUGGUCAAUGUCUGGUCUGGGUCCAGUGUUCCUUCCCAAACUGUGGGAAAUGGAGGCGGCUGUGUGGGAACAUUGACCCCUCAGUUCUCCCAGAUAAUUGGUCCUGUGAUCAGAACACAGCAGAUGUGCAGUAUAAUCGCUGUGAUAUUCCUGAGGAGACCUGGACAGGGCUUGAGAGUGAUGUGGCCUAUGCCUCCUACAUCCCAGGAUCCAUCAUCUGGGCCAAGCAAUACGGUUACCCCUGGUGGCCAGGCAUGAUAGAAUCUGAUCCUGACUUAGGGGAAUAUUUUCUUUUUACUUCCCAUCUUGAUUCCCUGCCGUCUAAGUACCAUGUGACGUUUUUUGGAGAAACAGUUUCUCGUGCAUGGAUCCCAGUCAACAUGCUAAAGAACUUCCAGGAGCUGUCCCUGGAGCUAUCAGUCAUGAAAAAGCGCAGAAAUGACUGCAGCCAGAAACUGGGGGUGGCCCUGAUGAUGGCUCAAGAGGCAGAACAGAUCAGCAUUCAGGAACGGGUUAACUUGUUUGGUUUCUGGAGCCGAUUCAACGGAUCUAACAGUAAUGGGGAAAGAAAAGACUUACAGCUCUCUGGUUUGAACAGCCCAGGAUCCUGCUUAGAGAAAAAGGAGAAAGAGGAAGAGUUGGAAAAGGAGGAAGGAGAGAAAACAGACCCAAUUUUGCCCAUUCGUAAGCGAGUCAAAAUACAGACCCAAAAAACCAAGCCAAGAGGGCUUGGGGGUGAUGCAGGCACAGCAGAUGGCCGAGGCAGGACACUGCAGAGGAAGAUAAUGAAGAGAUCUCUAGGCAGGAAAUCCACAGCUCCUCCUGCACCCAGAAUGGGAAGGAAAGAAGGCCAAGGGAAUUCAGAUUCUGACCAGCCAGAAUGAAUGAAAAUUAGAAUGAAAGAGCGUCUCGGACUGCACCCAGCACACACUAUAGAAACAGAAUGAUUCCUGAUUUGAUUUGGCCCAGGGGCAGGAGAAUGGUAGAAGAGAAGUAACACUUAAUCAGUAUUGCCAAGGGCUGGCUAAAGAGAUACUUCCAUGCCUGCUCCUUUAAAUUUUUUUCAAUAGCUCUCUCACUGGAUAUUCCCAUUUUAGAUAUUAGAAAACUGAGGCUCAAAGGAUUUAAAAAGUGCUCAAGGCUGGUGACUAGCAUAGGGCAGACGGCUUGACUCUCUUUCUGAUCCCAAAGUCCAUAUUCUUUGUAUUGAGAAAGGUCAUCUUUUCCAGAGAUUUCUUGGAAAUAGAGAUUUAGGAGUUUGACUUAUAAAAGGUAAGGACAGGCUGACCUAAUAGGACUCUUGGCUUUGUCACCUUCUCAUUUAGGCCCUAAGAAAAAAUUUAAAGCUCCCCAGAGCAAGGCCUUGGCAGCCAGCUUUUCAGAGGGAAAAGAAGUUAGAACAGUGCCAAAGAACCUGGGCCUAUCAGCGUGUAAGGGGGCCUGCCCCUCAUCUGCGAAAGAAGAGCCCAGACACCGGGAACCCCUGACCCAGGAGGCUGGAAGUGUCCCCCUUGAGGACGAAGCCUCCAGUGACCUGGACCUGGAGCAACUCAUGGAAGAUGUUGGGAGAGAGCUGGGGCAGAGCGGGGAGCUGCAGCACAGCAACAGUGAUGGCGAGGACUUCCCCGUGGCGCUGUUUGGGAAGUAGCUGGUGCUCCUCUGCUCCCUCUUUUUCUCCCUUCUCUGGGGCGCAGGAGGGAGAAGUUGCUAAGUGCUGGGUCUGUUCAUUGGCUAUGAGGUUCAAAUGUGUGUGGUGCAGUUUCUGUGUUAAUAAAGCAGGUUACAGUCGA